GUCCUCUUUCAGCAGCAGCAGCCGGAGCCGCCGCCGCAGCCCGGUGGGGCAACCCUGACUCGGACCGCUCGGGAGAGCCCCAGGAGAGGCCAGCGCCGCGCAGCAGCCGCCCCGCUGCGCCCACCUCCCCGGCUGCUCCCGGAGGGCUCACAAAGGCGGUGGCCGCCCGAGUGGCCUUCUCCAUCCAGGCGUUCGCGUCCUCCUCCCCACCUUCUCUCCCGAAGGCGAAAAUGGCAGGGCCAGGCGAGAACCUGGGACAGCGGUGGCCCUAGCCCUGCGAUCCUCACCCCUCCUGCUAGGAGAGGCUGCGGGCUGCCCGCGGACGAUGUGGCCGCGGCUGCUCCCGAGCGCAUCUUCGGCCCGGGUCCCCGCCGCCACCCCUCUUCUCUGCUCCUUCCAUCCCGCCCAGAGGAGUUGAUGCCGCUGUCGCCGCCGCCGCCGCUGCUGAAGCCGCGGCUGAUGGAUGCCAGGGAGUGCCGCAUUGCUUAGCGACCCCGCCUCUGGGUUUGCUGAUGAUCUCUCUCCGCCCUGGAGCUCAGCGCUGAAGAGCUACCUUAUUAUUAAUCAGAAUUUCCAUCGCCACCCCUGGCAGGCGUAUCCUUCAGCAGGGACCGCAGGAACAUUCACAGUGCAGGGGCUGAGAUGUGCGUGGGGGUUGUUUUUGUUACAUCUUGGAAGAGAAGAGAAGAGGACAGUACCAAGAUCAGAAACACCCGUGCUAGGUGGAAUUAGGGGUGAUUUGUUAGGAAAGAGAAAGGACAAGAAGAGGAGUGCGGAGCCCUUCAGGGGUUCACAUCUCUUUAAAGGAAAGGAAAGAGGGAGCCAAAGUAGGGUGUUGUAUUUUAGGGGGCAGAGGAAGAAGUUUACACCCCCCGGCCCCCCCAGCUUUGCUGGGGGAAAGCAGGAGCAACAGGGCACUUGAUUGGACACCAAGAUUAUUAAUUUCCUGUAGGGGAGAGGAAGCAGGCAGCAGGAGGUCUGGGGGCUGGAGUCUGGUGGUGGCAAGGACCAGGUUUGCUUUGGGACAGUCAACAAGGUCUUCUGAGGGAAAGCUCAGAGAUAGGCAGAACAAUGACUCAUUUGCAAGCCGGUCUCUCCCCUGAGACCCUGGAGAAAGCUCGCCUGGAGCUCAAUGAAAACCCAGACACGCUGCACCAGGACAUCCAGGAGGUGAGGGAUAUGGUCAUCACCAGGCCGGACAUUGGCUUUCUGCGCACGGAUGAUGCCUUCAUCUUACGCUUCUUGCGGGCUAGGAAGUUUCAUCACUUUGAGGCCUUCCGCCUCCUGGCGCAGUACUUUGAGUACCGGCAGCAGAACCUGGACAUGUUCAAAAGCUUUAAGGCCACCGACCCUGGCAUCAAGCAGGCACUGAAGGAUGGCUUCCCUGGGGGCCUGGCCAAUCUGGACCACUAUGGCAGGAAGAUUCUAGUCCUUUUUGCUGCCAAUUGGGAUCAGAGCAGGUACACACUGGUGGAUAUUUUGCGUGCCAUCUUACUUUCUUUAGAAGCCAUGAUUGAAGAUCCUGAGCUUCAAGUGAAUGGGUUUGUUUUGAUCAUAGACUGGAGUAACUUCACUUUCAAGCAAGCCUCUAAACUCACACCAAGUAUGCUGCGAUUAGCUAUUGAAGGCCUGCAGGAUAGUUUCCCAGCGCGAUUUGGAGGAAUUCAUUUUGUCAAUCAACCAUGGUAUAUCCAUGCCCUGUACACCGUGAUCCGGCCUUUCCUGAAGGAGAAAACUCGGAAAAGGAUAUUUUUGCAUGGUAACAACCUGAACAGUCUACACCAACUAAUUCAUCCUGAGAUCCUGCCCUCUGAGUUUGGAGGAAUGCUGCCUCCUUAUGACAUGGGGACAUGGGCAAGAACACUGCUAGACCAUGAAUAUGACGAUGACAGCGAGUACAAUGUAGACUCCUACAGCAUGCCUGUGAAGGAAGUAGAGAAGGAACUCUCCCCAAAGUCCAUGAAGAGAUCUCAAUCAGUAGUGGAUCCUACAGUACUAAAACGCAUGGAUAAAAAUGAGGAAGAAAACAUGCAACCAUUGCUUUCUCUGGACUAAUAACUUCUCUACAUCCCCUUCAUGGAUUAGAAAUGGAAAGUAUUGGUUUUCAGCAACAGGGACAACACUGUAGAGGAAUUACCAGCUGGAAACCGACUUAUUCAUGUUAAUGUAGCAUAAUAUAUAACAAGGCAUCAGGCUUUCCUUGGCCUGAACCAUGGGGGCCCUGGGCUGGAUUUUUAAAAUGUCAAUAAUUUAUUCUGUAAGUGCCAAGUUGUUUGUAAAUAUAAUGUAAUCUUCAUGUCAAGUUUGUAAAUUUCAGUAGUAACUCAGUUUGGAAAAAGGUUGGCUCAAAAGUCCAUGCCAGUGUUAUGAACUAUAACAAAAAGCAGAAAAGACACAGUCAAAGCUAAUUAAAUGUAGCCCUCUUUCCUAUGAAGCCAUAUUUCAGCUCUCAUAGUGAUUGUUUCAUUGUUUUUCUCUGAAACUCUGUCAGUAUUCAAACAUACUCUUAACGGGCACACACAACUAAGUGAUUCCAGGAAAUUUUAUGAUUAAUGUAUUUCCUGUCUAGUGAUUUUCAUUUCAGAGAAAUGUGUCUUAGUAACUAUCAUUGGCCUUGCAUUUUGGAGGCAAGGAAUGGCAGAUGAGCUGGUAAACUGAACACUUGAACUCUUCUAUGUUGUUUAAUUCUUGGAAUCUUGUGAAAAGAUGUGUUUCCUCAAUUAAGACGUAGAAAUGUAAAAAAGAGUGGAUUCUUUUUAAAUUGCUGUCUUCACAAUGUGCCCUUUAUUCAAGACCCUAUUAUAUUUCUUCCUAAUGUACUCUAAGUACAUUUCCCCUCCAAAACUCUUUGACUAAGAGAAUGAGAACUCAUGUGAACAGUGUUCUGACAGCUAAUUUUGAACAUAAAAUUUUCCACUUACAGAUGAGGGGCUAAUUUCUAAUUGUUGUGCACUGGUUAAAAAGUAUAUAUAUAUAUAUAUUCACACAUAUAUAUUUUUACUGAGCUCUAAUAAAUCCUUAAUGUGACAGGCUUAUAAAAUAAAUCAUAGAUAUUCAAUGAUCUUAUGGAUAAUUACAUGAGAUAACUCUGGAAAACUACUUCCACUGAAGUUAAUGAAAAGGAGAAAUAGUGAAACUGACUUUCAGUGUACCUAUUUAAAGGAAUUCCAAGUUAAUUUAUAAUGCAAUCUUACAUAUGUGCCAUCUUAUUUGAACUAUAUUUUUCCUUCAAAGAAGCAAUAGGUCUCAACAUAGUGUAGGUAGCAUCAGGUGACAGAAAGCCAAUUUUAUUUUCAAAUUUAAGUUAAUUAUCUUCGUGAUCCUAUUUAUCCACAAUUUCUUUCAGAAAAGACUGAAAAAACACAUUAUAUUCAGGAGAUAUAAUGAAAUUAUUGGAAGGCAUCUAUGACAACAUGUAAUCAUUUAUACGUGGAUUUAGAAAUUUGCAUAUUUAACAUUUUAUUUCAUAAAAUUUAUACAAUUACAGCAAAUCUUAAUUUUUUAAUUUUAAAUUUCAAUGUGAAAAAAUGAUUUUUAUCACCCAUAAUAAAUUUUGAGAUUGAGAGUUUACCAUUAAAGUAUUCUUUUGGAAGAAAAAUAUCUCAGAAACUCUUGGAAACCAACAAAAAUAAAGGCAUGUGUCAGCCUUCAUAUUUUUUGGCCAAAAGCUCCCAAAAUUUGUUAUAAUUCUGCAGCCAAAAAUUGUAAAAGCAAGCUGAAUACACCAAUGUACAGUGUAUCAAUGGACUGCCUCAUGUGUGUAAAAAUACAUUAAUUAACACAAAUGAAAGAUACCUUAAUAAUGCCAACCUCCAGUCAAGUGCAGAAGAAUAAUGACUGUCAGGCACUCUGCUCUCCUUGUGACUUUUACAGAGAUUGGAAUGCACUGGGGACAACAUGUCUCAGCAGUUCUUACCUUUAUAAGAAUUCUAACCAUUGAUAUUCUUACAUUCUUGCCUACCUGACAUACAUUUUGUAGCCAUGGGCUUUUUAGACUAUAUAAAUCUUAGGCAGUAUAAUCCAUUGGAAUAAAAUAGAAACAUUGUAAGUGCAGAGGGCAGUCAACUUUUCAUUCUCAUGAGUUUCUCUUGAUGUGUACCAUUUAUUGCCAGUUUUCAGAAUUCUGCCAGUUUCAGAUGUCAACCAGCAUUGGCAGCUUCUUUCCCCUAUCGUAAAGUUAGUGUCAUAUAUAAAAAUAACUAGAAAGGCAUAUUUUAUAUGUAUGCCUAUCUAAUUAUAAGUAUCAUUCACACUGUCUCCCAGACCCACAUUUGGAAAGUUUGCAUUGCAUUACUGCUCAUCUUUAGAUGAGCAAUUGAGAGUUGGCUAGAUUGUGUAAAAUAUUUUAAAAUGAAUGAACAAAUUACAAUGAUGAUGCCUUUUGAAAUUACCAUAUCUAGUUCAUUCUGUGAAUAAACUCAUUUUCUAGUAAUGUUUGUGAACCUUAGUCAAGGGAUAUUCAUUCAACUUUAUAAAUUUACCCCUCAGCACCAGCUAUCUAGCACUGUUUAGGAAUUUUUCCCUUCAUGAUAUUCUGUGUCACAUCCUAUGUCUAUGAAUAACCUAUACACUAUAGUUGUAUGCCUAUAAGCACUCCUAUACUCUUGUAUUUUAAUUGCAAUAGUAUACCUCCACUCUCUCUCUCUCUCUCAUACACACACACACACACACUCUUACACACACACUAACACACUAGACUGUUUGCCCUAAUGAAUUUUCCUCUGUACUUCGAGAGCUAUUUUAGUUGUCUUGUCACUUGAAAUUUGCGGGCUUCAAAGAAUUAUCGCAUUUGACUUGGAAUGGUCCAGUAGUCCAUUUACUUCUUUCACCCUGCCUGUUCCAUCUUCUAUUUCUGAUAUUUUUUCUUUCUUCCAGUUAUUUCAGGGGCAGGUGAUUCCAAAGCUGGUUUAAAAAUAAAUAACUUCUCUUAUGUUGUCAGUGAUGUUUGCCUGCAUUUUUGACUACUAUUUAAGAGGGAAGAGAUUAUCAUGAAAAUAUACUCUAAGAAAUAUGAAGAAGUGCCUCUUUGAAAAUGGAAUAAAGCAACGUUACUGGCAUAUGGAUUUUAUUUGUACUCUCUUCCAAAAAGUAAAUACGUAAAUCUAUAUUAUAUAGGUGAAAUAUAGAUAUCAUUUGAAGAAGGAUAUUUAAGGCCUUUAUUUGAACAUACUCAUACAGUAUUAAGUCUCUGUUGUGUAAGUUAAAUACAGUAACUUUAGUACAUGUUAAUGAUAAACGUGGCACUAGGCUAAAACGAUAUACGAGUAUUAAACAGAGUUUUGCAAGCAAGUUUUUGAAGUGGGCAUGCAUGAAUUCUUUCAUUUCAGUAAUGGUUUGCAUAAGUGUAGACAGAGAUAUUUCCUAAGUUUUUUCAUAUAGAAUACUUAUUUACUUUAUAGUACCAAAAAUUCAUACAUUCAUAAGCAGGAAAGCCAAAAAUUCAUACAUUAAUACUUAGCUUUUUUAAUACUGUUAACUAGGUCAUAUUGUUAAACAUGUGAAGCGUCUGUAAUAUUCCUGAGGGAAAAGAGGUCCCUCUAUUGCAUCAAGAAAUUGGAGAGUUGUUUUAGACAUUGGGGAAUAUGUUUAUGACUCUUCACAUAAAGAAACCUUCAGAGCCAUGGAGUAUGUCUUCAGGGACAGGGAUCAUUUGCUUCUACAAUGUAAAGGUUUAUGGACAUAUCUCUGGUCCUUUAAAGAAGUUACAUUAAGAAAGCUUGCUGAGAGGCUGUACACUCUUCUGUUGUUUUAUUUAAAGGUCUGCCUUGUGUGGUUGGUGAAUAAUAUCUCAGCUUCUUUUUUUGUGUAUAUUUAUUAAUGAUUACAUGAAAAGUUGCCAUCAGCCAUGAGGACACUUCAAAAAUUUUCAACACACUAAAUAAAAUGAGCAGAGCUCUAGCAUGAUAUUUGAACUUUCAGAUAUGGUAUAUGUACAUUUUUUACAACAAUAAGCUCAUAGGCAUAUAUUCCAUUGUAGAUCUGCUAUAUAAAUACAUAGCCUGAAACAUAGUAAUGCAUUUGAAAUUUGUGAGGUCACUGAUCAUACAAGAAGAGGCAGAUUAUAAACCAACAUAUUGGAACAAAAGAAGAUUGGUUAAAUAUGCAAGGUGUGUAAUUAUCUUCAGUAAUGAAAAGGAUUUGUUUUCUUGUUUUUGUCUUUGGUUUUAGUUGAAAAAAUAGCUUCCCAUAUGCUACUGGAACUAUUUGACAUUAUUUGCUACAUGAAAAAAGGCAAAUAAGUAAACAUACAAAAGAAGCUUGGCUUUGUAACAUUAUUAUAUUAUGAUCUCAAUGGCUUAGAGAAUAUAAUCUUUUUUAAGAAUUAAAGAUUUUAUUUUAUAAAUAUUUGGAGGUUAACAUAGGACAUGAAAAUAGUGCUGUGGAUUCUGUUAUGUACUAACUAUGGGAAUGAAUUCUCCAGUACCAUAGGAAAAUAUAUAAGAUAACAACUUUGUGGAUUGAAACACUCAAAUUAGCCUUUUUUUCAAGGAAGCAGGUGUACAAAUGAUGCUAUUGAAAUAAAAAAAUGUAGAAAUCACUUAAUUAUAGGAGUUAAAUAUAAUCAAUGCACUCAUGGUAAAUAAUGGAAAUUGUUAAAAUUUAGAAGAGUUUUGUCAUUAUUUGACUUAGAUUUAAGUCUCAGUGCAAAUAUGUCUGUCCUUGAUAUAGUGCAUUUAUUCUGUAAGACUUAUUUUACCUGGUGAACGAGAUGGACUUAGGUGAAAAUAAAUUUUAACCACAGUUUUAAGGGUCACCCAAUCCUCAACUACUUUAAAAAAUUGCAAUGAAUUUUAAUUCAUUUACUUUUAACAGAGAUACAAAGCACUGUCUUGUUUCUAAUCCAAUUUUUCAAUUUUUCAGAUUUUAUAUUUGCUUAAACAAUAAAUAAAACUCAGAAAACCAAAUAGUUUUUGUUUUCAAAGCUAUCCAGGAAAAAUAAAAGAUGUCUAACAGGAAAUCAUACAAGUCCUUGAAGAAUACUGAGUAUAUUAUUUGCUAUUUUACUCAAAUGUUAUUAAUUUUUACUACUACAAACUACUUAUUUAGUACUACACGGCAUUUACUAUUUGGCCUUUUGAAGGAGUUAUAAAUUCCAAAACACUAUAAUAUAAUUUUUGGACAAGUAUACAUUUCUGUUUAAAAGAAAUGUAUGCUUUUAUUUUGUAUAUUUUAUAUUUUAAAUGUAUACAUUUAUUUUGCACAUUGUUAAUGUUAAAUUUGGUAGUCCUGGAUCUGCUGCAUCUAUAAAAUGGAGAUUUCUUUAAAAAAUCGUCUAAAAAUUAGCAAUAUUUUUAUUUUGAGAGAAAUUGUGCUUAGCUAUUUAAGUUAAGAUUCCUCAAGUUUGUGAUAUUUGUAUGUGUGGGGAUCAAAGAGGAAAAUAUAUAGUAAUUUGUUUCAUCAAAAUGACGUAUUCAAUAUUCUAUAACUUCUAGUCAAACUUUCAAAUGAAAGUUUGAAAGAAGUAAACUAAUGUUUUAAUUACAUAUAGCAAAGGAAUGAUCAGUAAAUAAAAUAACUAGGGUUUUCACAUUUGCAAUAGAAUGACUGGAUUAGGCAAGAGAUUAAAUUUAGAAAUUUGAAUUACAGAAAAGCAUUGGUUUAAAUAAAUCCUCAAAAAAGUAAUCCCAGGUCAAAAUAUGAUGUGAAAUUAAAAAAAAAAUUCAGCCUGAUUUGAGAAAGAAUGCUUACUCAAUAAAUAUGUAUUUGUGUCUUCUGUGAGUUUCCCUCAUUUAUCCUAUCUGUGGAUGAAAAGUCAUCUAAUAAGGUAUAAGAGACUCAAUUACAUUUACCUAGAACCAUCUACAAGUAGACUUCAUGAAUUUCUUUGGCUCAAACUCAGAGGAUUUUCUUUACACAGGAUUCUUGAGGUUAUCAAGAAUCGUUAUUGCUGCUCCCUCCUAAAGGCAGGCCAGGAGAAGCCACAUUUCCAGCAGUAGUAUCCUCAGUGGGAAUGAACCAGAAAACAAAGAAAAAGCCAGAGAUAUUGUCUCCACUCUCGUUACAAAAAAGUGCGUUCCUUCUUCAGGAGGAUCGAGUAGAAAAUAUUUUCUACUCGAAGAGGCCAUGGGGAAGUGAUGGUCAAAUCUCUGUUGUGAAGCAAGUUUCCACACAGAAACAUCAUCAAAAACACGUACCUCUGAGCAUCACUUCUUUCUCUAAAAAUAAAAAUAAAUAUGCUGUUUUCCUCCCUUUUUUCUAAUUGGCAUCAUAAAAGUAUAAGAAGCCACAAAUGCAUUGUUGCCACUUAAGAAAAAAAUCCUAUGUUAUACAUAUAUGAACAUAAUUCACUUAGUUGCAUAUGAUUGAAAUAUUUGCAUGCUGGUUUAUAAAUUAUUACCUAAAAGUUUUAUGAAAUAUAAUUAUUAAGUUUUAGUGCUAGAAAAAUUGUUGUUUUUUGUGUUUUGUAUUCAUAGGGAAGACUAGUAAUAUCCCUUACUCCUCAUUCAUAUAGCUAACAAUUUUAAUUGGAUGGCUAAUGGAUAUGGCGGAUUUAACAUUUACAAAACCAAACUACUUUCACUCUGACCCUGCUUCCCCUUUAGCCUUCUCAUCUCACUAUGUGUCGACCCCAAUCUUCCAGUUUCUAGGAAUAAAAAUUUUGGAGUCAUCCUCUCUUUCCUUCCUCUUUUUCUUUCAAAACUACAUCACAUCAGCUAGCUCAUGCUGUUGGGUCUUCAAAAUAUAUCCACACUCUAACCACUUCUCCAAUCUUCUUCACUGUAUUGGACCAAGUCUUCAACAUUUUCCAUCUGGAAUAUUUUAAUAAUCUAAAAACUAGUCUUCUUGCUUCCAGAGUCAAUUUUCAACACAUUAGCAAGAGUGAGUCUCUUAAAAUGUAACUCAGACCAUUUUGUUCUCCAAACCCUCUGAAAGAGUAAAAGCCGAUGUCUUUAUAUCAGUGUAUGAGAAGUCUUGAUAUGAAGGCAGUAAGCACCAGUACAGCAACAUAGCAUGGUUUCUGAUUGGGCUGGCAUUUUUGCUGGUACUAUGAAAAAAUAGUUGUUAAAUACUUUAAUUUCUUGCUUCUGAAGUUCUCUACCCCGUUCUUGCCUUUUCUUAGAUAAUCUCUUAAGAAUCUCUCCUUUAUUUACUGCUGCCAAACUGUCAUCUUUGCUGUUCCAGGAACUUGCUAAGCAUGCCUCUACCUCAGGACUUUCGCAUUUCUGUUCCCUUUGCCUCUAAUUUCAGAUAUCCACGUGGUUUAUUCCCUCAUCUUCUUCAGGUAUUUGCUUAAAUGUCAUCUUCUUUGUGAGGACUCUCUUUCCUAAUUUUAGAUGAAACAGCCCUGUGGUUCUUCAUAUUCUCCUUUCCUGCUGUAUUUCCUCUCCAUAGCAUUUAUCACCUGAUACACCAUACAGAUUAUUUAUUUACUUUGCAUUUCCCCCCAAUAGCAAUGUGAACUCCACAAGGGCAGGAAUUUUUGUCUGUUUACUACUGCAUUACUGGUGCCUUGUACAGUCCCUGGAACUUAACAAAUCCAAAAUGAUUUCAUGAGGAUCCUAAUUUGUUUCAGCAAGUUAUGUAACGGCCAAUAGUAUGAAUUGAAAGAGUUUCUUGUUGUCUUAAUUUAAAAAAUUUUGUUAUUUAUCUUCAAAGGGGAAAUUUUACCCUCUCAUGAUAAUAGAAUCAUGAAUCAAAAAUGAUAUCCUCUUCUCCCCAAUUGUGAUCUCUAUCCCUGAGCCUAAGUUUUACAUCAGUAUUUCAGUUUUGUCUUUAGAAGUUACUCAACGAUCACUGGACCCUAUAUCUAUCCACAUGGCUUACUCUUGGAGAGACUACAAGAUAGCUCAGGGGAAAAGUCAUUUUGAGAUUAAAACUACAUGGAAUUGUUCUUUAUGGAUUAUCAUGGUUAAUUUCAAUUUUUAAAAAUAUGCAGGAAGUUAAAAGACUAUAAUUCCAGUAUUGGAAGCCAGUUUAAGAGAAUAUGACUAUGUAGUUACUUUUAAUGGAAAGGGGAAGAAGAGGAAGAAAAAGGAAAGACAUUGUGUUCGUAUCUUCUCUGCAACAAUUAUAAAAUGAAUGAGGAAGUAUUUUGGUGUUUCUAAGGUCUUUCCAUGAUCUUGAAAUCUAUAUAUUAUAGUCAUUUAGUCUGUGAACCAUUUUAACAAUUGGGUUUCAUGUUACAUAUCUUUAAAUUUUUAUGUUGAAAAUUUAUAGCUGUGACACAAGAUGAUAGAAAUUGCUCAUGCUCACAUAUAUUCCAACUGGCUUUUCAGCUUGCUCCCUUCUCUUUUAAUUUCAGCUAUCAUUUUUAGAGCCUUACAGUCACAAUUGUUCUUAACUAUCCCAAAUUUUUAUUUCCUAUUUGGACUGACUUCUCCAUAAUUUUAGUAACUAAAUGACCUAGAUAUUGGUUCUUGUUGUGAUAGGUUUCUGAUUUGUAUCCUUUGCAGUUUAACUUUUAAUCCUUACCAAACAUAUGUUAUUCCUUUUCUUCAGCUACAUUGUUGUGCCUUUCCCAACACUGUAAUAAUUUAAGCCUCCUGUUUUAUAAUCUUCUAUCAGAACAUAUAUUAAGAAGACACUGAAUUUAAAGAAUCAGCAGGUGAUGUUGAAGAAGAAAUAUAACCUGAAAUAUAAGAAUAGAUGUUUGAAACUGUUUCAGAAGUUAACCAGUCUUUUAGUGGCUUUGUAAUGGGUAGGGGUUUUAUUCCUCUUUGUGUGCUAUGUAGGACAUUGUUAACCAAUAUAGAUUAUGUUUCUUGUCAGUUACACAAGGAUAGGUAAUCAGGGUUAACAGUUCGGAAAACAUUCUCUAGAGAAGAGACUAAUGAUUCUUGCUCACAAACAAGGCAGAAUUUCCUUAUGUUUCUUAAUAUUUGAUCCUUGAUAGUCUGUACAGUGGAAACCAUUUCCCUCUGUGAUAUCCUUUUUUGCCAACCUAUAUGAAUGUGUUUAGCGUCACUUCAGAUAUAGAGUUCAAGCUCAAGUAUACACAGCACAUGAAAGAUCCUAUAGUUCAUGUUCUCUUAGGUUGAAUUUUCUUUUCAUAAUUUUUUAUGAUUGAAUUCUAAGGGUAUGUUCCUUGGUAAAUUGUGUUAAUUAUGUCCACUUUAUAAUGGAUUUAACAAUUUUACAAAGCAGAUCAUUGUUUAUUAUAUUCUGAAAACCAUUAUAUUAAUAUUUUAUUUCUUUUUUUGCAGAGAAACUAUUGUCUUUUUUGAUUUCUGAGGAUGAAUGAAGUACUGUUAAAUAAAAUGUCACUAAAUGAAACUUCA